GCACACUCGCGCACACUCGCGCUCGGGCGCACACGGAGCAGGGACCGGCGCCCGGAGCGAGCCAGGGAGCGGCUAACCGGGGACCCACCGCGCGGAGCCAGCCUAGCUGCCAGCGAGCCCAACCCGCGACGACCCACGCCCCUGAGCCCCGCAGCCGACCCCUGCCGGCCGGUGUCCCCACCGCCAUCCCUGACCCAUGGCGCUGAAGAGGAUUCAGAAAGAAUUGAGUGAUCUACAGCGCGAUCCACCUGCUCACUGUUCAGCUGGACCUGUGGGAGAUGACUUGUUCCACUGGCAAGCCACUAUUAUGGGGCCUCCUGAUAGCGCAUAUCAAGGUGGAGUCUUCUUUCUCACUGUACAUUUUCCGACAGAUUAUCCUUUUAAACCACCAAAGAUUGCUUUCACAACAAAAAUUUACCAUCCAAACAUAAACAGUAAUGGAAGUAUUUGUCUCGAUAUUCUGAGGUCACAAUGGUCACCAGCUCUGACUGUAUCAAAAGUUUUAUUGUCCAUAUGUUCUCUACUUUGUGAUCCUAAUCCAGAUGACCCCUUAGUACCAGAUAUUGCACAAAUCUAUAAAUCAGACAAAGAAAAAUACAACAGACAUGCAAGAGAAUGGACUCAGAAAUAUGCAAUGUAAAAAUCAAAAACAUUUUCAUAUAUACCAGAGUACUGUAAAAUCUAGGUUUUUUUCAACAUUAGCAGUAAAUUGAGCACUGUUUACUGUUUCAUUGUACCAUGAAACCAUUUGAUUUUUACCCAUUUUAAAUGUGUUUCUGAAGCAAGACAAAACAAACUUCCAAAAAUACCCUUAAGACUGUGAUGAGAGCAUUUAUCAUUUUGUAUGCAUUGAGAAAGACAUUUAUUAUGGUUUUUAAGAUACUUGGACAUCUGCAUCUUCAGCUUACAAGAUCUACAAUGCAGCUGAAAAGCAACCAAAUUAUUUUUUGCUGAAACUAGAUGUUUUUACAUGAGAAAUACUGUAUGUGUUGUCUAAGAUGUCAGUUUUAUAAAUCUGUAUUCAGAUUUCAUUCUUUGUUAGCUCACUUUAUAAUUUGUAUUUUUUUACUGUAUAGACUAAAUAUAUUCUAUUUACAUGUAUGUCAACUCAUUACUUUUUUCCUGUGAACAGUAUUGAAAAACCCCAACGGCUGAUAAUUAAGUGAAUUAACUGUGUCUCCCUUGUCUUAGGAUAUUCUGUAGAUUGAUUGCAGAUUUCUUAAAUCUGAAAUGAUCUUUACACUGUAAUUCUCAGCAUACUGAUUAUGGAGAAACACUUGUUUUGAUUUUGUUAUACUUGACUUAACUUUAUUGCAAUGUGAAUUAAUUGCACUGCUAAGUAGGAAGAUGUGUAACUUUUAUUUGUUGCUAUUCACAUUUGAAUUUUUUCCUGUAUAGGCAAUAUUAUAUUGACACCUUUUACAGAUCUUACUGUAGCUUUUUCCAUAUAAAUAAAAUGCUUUUUCUACUAUUUGUCUUGAUUACUUAAAAAAAUAAAAAUAUAAGUAAGGAUCAAAACUCUAAAAUUUUGCAUGAAAAUUACAUCCAAAUUGUGAAAAUCAGAUCUAUUUUGUUUGCCAUUAGUCACCAUUAGUUAUAUAAAUUUUAUUGUUUUAGGUUAGUAUCUCUUUACUAAAUUGUCAGUCUAUAAGAUAAUAUAUGUUGAUCCCUUGCUGUAGAGGAGAAUUUAGAGUAAUUUGGGGUUUGUCUUGGAUUAUAUCUAAAUGGAUUAUUUGUUAAAAGUACUGAAAUGAGUAUAAGGCAGUAUCACCCAUCCAAAAGAAAGGUCUUUAUAGACCUGCACAGUCACUAGAUUAAUUCAUUAAAAUGCCCCCACCCUGAUGUAAUUGACAUUACAUUUCUUAACAUUUUAAAAUCUAGAAUUUCUAAAAUGGAAUUUAAUGCCAUCACAAUUUGAAAAACUUUUUUUUUUUUUUUACUAUAGAAGUUACAAAGGAAGUUCUAAAAUUAUGCCUCCCUCUGUUUUUAUAAGUUGCCAUCGAAAAGUGAUUUAAAUAAGCAGGUUAUCUUUAUAGAUUUUAAAGAAAACUAGAAAGUUUUAAUGUUUUAACUUGGGGAAAAAUACAUCUCUUUAAUGUUUAGCAUGCUUGUCAACCUUGAGUGAGUGUCAUUUUUAAGAACAGUUGUAGCCCUUCUGAUUAUUGCAGUAGCUGUAGAAGUAUGUAAGAAUAUGUGAUGGGUGUAGUCAUUAGCAAAGCAUUUAAAUCACUUGAGUAUUUUGUCAUGGUUCAUUAUUAUUAAAGCACAAAAUAACCUAUUGUUAGAAAAUAUGUGUUUUUAUAAAUGAAUGUAAAAUAAUUAAAUGAAUUGUGAAAUGGAUGUUUAAGAAAAUAUAGGCUUAAAAAGUAAAUCUAUAAAAUGAUGUCUUAAAACAGCCAUAUCAUGAAAAAUUCUACUUAGCUAUAUUAUUAUAAGCUACAUUUGCCCUGAAUUUGAACACUCAACAUCACUAGAUUUAAAUAUUUAGUAUAUUUUGAUAGUAAAGGGUUUUGUUUCUUGAAUAUCUUCACUUUAAACAAAAAAAAAAAACAACUUUCAUUUGUGUGGCAUUUAUUUUUGGAAGUGUCUUCUUUUUUUUCUUUAUUAAAGUUUUUGAAACUUG